GCUCCCUCACCACCCUGCCUGGCUUGGCAGGAGUCGUCUGAGAAGGGGACUCCUCCAGGGACUUGGUCCCUAGGUCCCCAGAUGGGGAGACUGAGGCCGUGGCUGUGUGUCCCUCUGAGAGUUGGAGCGGGGCUGGGCCCGAAUUCGACCGCAGCAGGAUUCUCUCUCAUUUCUGAGCCCCGGAGGUGGCAGAGCGGCAGACCCGGGCAAGUGAACCCUAGGGCUGCAGGAGCCCAGGCCCCGACGCCGGCGCAGAGGGGACGGAAGGGCCCGCCCCCAGCCCAGCGUGCACAGAGGCCAUAGCCAAGGCCUUAAGGCUCAUCCAACCGGGGACUCAUAUCCCCCCCACCGGCAGCCCGGCGCCCCAGCCUCUACCCGUGCCCGCCGAGAUGCUGCUGCCGCGGUCGGUGUCAUCGGAGCGGGCCCCUGGGGUGCCGGAGCCGGAGGAGCUGUGGGAGGCAGAGAUGGAGCGGCUGCGCGGCUCUGGGACGCCCGUGCGCGGGCUGCCCUAUGCCAUGAUGGACAAGCGCCUCAUCUGGCAGCUGCGGGAGCCCGCGGGGGUGCAGACCUUGCGCUGGCAGCGGUGGCAGCGCCGGCGGCAGACGGUGGAAAGGCGCCUGCGGGAGGCAGCGCAGCGGCUGGCCCGGGGCCUUGGGCUCUGGGAGGGGGCGCUCUACGAGAUCGGGGGCCUCUUCGGCACAGGAAUUCGGUCCUACUUCACCUUCCUCCGCUUCCUGCUGCUACUCAACCUGCUGAGCCUGCUGCUCACCGCAAGCUUCGUGCUGCUGCCCCUGGUCUGGCUCCGCCCCCCUGACCCAGGCCCCACCCUGAACUUGACCCUCCAGUGCCCUGGUAGCCGCCAGUCCCCGCCUGGCGUUUUGAGGUUCCACAAUCAACUUUGGCAUGUUUUGACUGGCAGGGCCUUCACCAACACCUAUCUCUUCUACGGUGCGUACCGAGUGGGGCCGGAGAGCAGCUCCGUGUACAGCAUCCGCCUGGCCUACCUCCUCAGCCCGCUGGCCUGCCUGCUCCUCUGCUUCUGUGGGACUCUGCGGCGGAUGGUGAAGGGGCUGCCGCAGAAGACUCUGCUGGGUCAGGGCUAUCAGGCGCCUCUCAGCGCCAAGGUCUUCUCCUCAUGGGACUUCUGCAUCCGGGUGCAGGAAGCAGCCACCAUCAAGAAGCAUGAGAUCAGCAACGAGUUCAAGGUGGAGCUGGAGGAGGGCCGUCGCUUCCAGCUGAUGCAGCAGCAGACCCGGGCCCAGACGGCCUGCCGCCUGCUCUCCUACCUGCGGGUCAACGUACUCAACGGGCUCCUGGUGGUUGGGGCCAUCAGCGCCAUCUUCUGGGCUACCAAGUACUCACAGGACAACAAGGAGGAGUCCCUGUUUCUGCUGCUCCAGUACCUGCCCCCUGGGGUCAUCGCCCUGGUCAACUUCCUGGGUCCCCUGCUGUUCACAUUUCUGGUCCAGCUGGAGAACUACCCUCCCAACACGGAGGUCAACCUCACUCUGAUCUGGUGCGUGGUGCUGAAGCUGGCCAGCUUGGGGAUGUUCUCCGUCUCCCUGGGUCAGACCAUACUGUGCAUUGGCAGAGACAAGAGCAGCUGUGAGUCCUACGGCUACAACGUUUGUGACUAUCAGUGCUGGGAGAACUCCGUGGGGGAGGAGCUGUACAAGCUGAGUAUCUUCAACUUCCUCCUCACCGUGGCCUUCGCCUUCCUGGUCACCCUGCCUCGGAGGCUGCUGGUGGACCGGUUCUCAGGCCGGUUCUGGGCCUGGCUGGAACGGGAGGAGUUCCUGGUCCCCAAGAAUGUGCUGGACAUCGUGGCGGGGCAGACGGUCACCUGGAUGGGCCUCUUCUACUGCCCCCUGCUGCCCCUGCUGAAUAGCGUCUUCCUCUUCCUCACCUUCUACAUCAAGAAGUACACCCUCCUGAAGAACUCCAGGGCAUCUUCGCGGCCCUUCCGUGCCUCCAGCUCCACCUUCUUCUUCCAGCUAGUGCUCCUCCUGGGCCUGCUUCUGGCUGCAGUGCCCCUGGGCUAUGUGGUCAGCAGCAUCCACUCCUCCUGGGACUGCGGCCUCUUCACCAACUACUCAGCACCCUGGCAAGUGGUCCCGGAGCUGGUGGCCCUUGGGCUCCCGCCCAUUGGCCAGCGUGCCCUCCACUACCUGGGCUCCCACGCCUUCAGCUUCCCCCUCCUCAUCAUGCUCAGCCUUGUCCUGACGGUGUGCGUCUCCCAGACCCAGGCCAAUGCCAGGGCCAUCCACAGGCUCCGGAAGCAGCUGGUGUGGCAGGUUCAGGAGAAGUGGCACCUGGUGGAGGACCUGUCGCGACUGCUGCCGGAGCCAGGCCCGAGCGACUCUCCGGGCCCCAAGUACCCUGCCUCCCAAGCUUCGCGCCCGCAGUCCUUCUGCCCCGGAUGCCCAUGCCCUGGCUCCCCGGGCCACCAGGCCCCGCGGCCGGGCCCCUCCGUCGUGGAUGCCGCGGGACUGCGUUCCCCUUGCCCUGGACAGCACGGUGCCCCGGCCUCCGCCCGCAGAUUCCGCUUCCCCAGCGGCGCGGAGCUGUAACCCCUACCCCUGCCUCCCCGAAGCCUCCCUGGGGCCCCUUCAGGCCUCCUUACUCCAUCUUCCAGACCCCUGGCGACCACCGCCCCUCUCAGUGGCUCCAGGGCCUCCCUCAGAGGUCCCCAAAGAUGGACACACAACCCCAGCGGCAGCAGGAAAAACAUAUGGGAAUUUUCUUUCUAUAUUUUAAUCUCAUCCCUUUAAAAUGUCUAUUUUUUAUUGUGUUUUUUAUAAUAUACAUAAUCUAUUAGUAUAGUAUCUCUUGAAUGCGAUUUUUUCUAGAAUGUGUUCUGCUGAUUUGUUUUAGAGCCAUGAGUGCAAUUUAUACACAUACAUCUAUUGGGAAUGCUCAGAAGUUGUUUACUGAUGGAAGUGCCUUCAGAAGAGUCCGGGAACCACUUCCUAAGGAAGGAAAGAGCUGGCCACAGUUAGAGCAAGCCUGCCUGGGGCCCUGCUCUGUGUUCCAGCUGCAAACUGCCUGCAUCAUCCCUUCCUGUUACUCUUCCUUCACCUGAGACAGUCGAGGCCACAGCGUCAGCCAGGGCCAGAGCUGGGAUUUGAACCCAGGCACUCGGGCUCCAGAGCCACACUGCCCCAGUGUGGGGCUUAGUGGCGGCUCCUGGCCCUGACUGAGGGGCUGACUGAAGCCUGGUGAGAGCGUGCUGGGUCAGCCUCUCCCUGGCGGGAAUCCUCUCCGUCCAGUCUUCUAACCUAGCAGCCUCACGUCCACAGAGCUGCCUUGUGAAACUCAGCAGAGCCCUGGCUUCCUGCAGAGCCGUGUUCUCCCAGCCUGCUUCAUGGCUCCCUGGUUGAGCCAAGCUUGCGGAUCCGUGGGGUGAAGGUACCCGCACCGCCUGGGCCUUAGUGGUAUGUACGGGCCUGCAUCGUGAGCAGCGGGCGGGGGCCCAGGCAGGUGAGGCAGCUGGCCACAAGGGCAGGGCCCGGCCCCCCUCCCAAGGCUGUGUCUGAUAUUCUUGAGCCUGUUCGAGUUUCCUUUUCCAAGCCUCCUGUUCUCCCACCCCCACCCCUGCCAUGCUGCAGUGACUAAAUCUGUGGUUCUCAUCCUUGGAGAACACCUGAGUAGCUGCUACAAGCUGGCCACAGCCCAGCGACUCUGAUGUGGUUGGGCUGGGUGUGGCCAGCAGCCAGGGCAUCGGGACUUUUCGAAGCUCCCAGGUGACUCACCGGCAGCUGGGGAUGAGAACUGUCAGGAGGGAAGGUCAGAAGUCCCAGGAUGCACUUGAAAAGCCUCUAGCUCCACCAGUGACCAGCUCCUGGCUGGACUCCUGGUCUGGACUCAGCAUCAGGGAGGCUCUGGCCUCUCGCCCUCAGGGCUGGGGGCUUCUUCACAUGGUCAUCAAAGACUUGGCCAGUUCCGCCUCUCCCACGGCCGUCCUUGUCUCACCCAGCAUCACGACGCAUCAGUUCACCAACAAACACGAUUCAGUGCUGCUAGUGCUGGGUCCUGUUCUGGGGGCUGGUGAUGAGGCCAAGAGGGAAAGAGGGAGCUCUGUGUUCCAUCGAGGGGGCGACAAGCCUGGACCAGAUGAAAGUGACUCAUGUUGUUAAUUAGCGGCUUAGGGCCAAAGGUGGCCCCUGGACCAGUGGCCUCAGCAUCACCUGGGAAAAGGUUAGAAAUGAACAUUCCCAGGCCCCACCUCAGCCUCCUGAAUCAGAGCAUCCCUUUGGCAAACCAUACUGAGAAACAACCACGUGCAUCACCAAGCGCUGUGAAGAAGGCAAGCUUUGAGACCUUGAAGGAAUCAUCAAACUCUGGGCCUCGGUGUGCUCACCCAGGGCGAGACAAAGACGCCAUGCUCCUCCAAGUGGCCUCCAAGAUUAAAUGAGCAAUGACUUUU